CCCGCUUUCCUGACUCCCAGGCGUCUUGCACCAAAGGGAGGUCGGGAUCUCGGUUUUCCGGCCCCGAGAGGGACCAGGUGCCUCCGCCAUAGCUUCUGUCGCUCCAUCGCCCGCACUGUGACUGGACUGUUAGAGGGAUCCGUGGAGAGGAGGCCAGGACACCUGGAAGCCGGGAAAUGGAUUCAGUGGUCUUUGAGGAUGUAGAUGUGAACUUCACCCAGGAGGAGUGGGCUUUGCUGGAUCCUUCCCAGAAGAAUCUCUACAGAGAUGUGAUGCAGGAAACCUUCAGGAACCUGGCUUCUGUAGGAAAAAAAUGGAAAGAUCAGAAAAUUGAAGAUGAGUACAAAAAUCCCAGGAGAAACCUAAGAGGUCUUAUGGGAGAGAGACUCUUAGAAAGUAAGAAAGAUCAUCAGCAUGGAGAAAUUUUGACCCAGGUUCCAGAUGACAUGCUGAAGAAGAAAACUCCCCGAGUAAAAUCAUGUGGAGAAGUCAGCGUGGGUCAUGCAUCCCUUAAUAGGCACCACAGAGCUGACACUGGACACAAGCCAUAUGAGUAUCAGGAAUAUGGACAGAAGCCAUAUAAAUGUACAUACUGUAAGAAAGCCUUCAGUGAUCUCCCCUACUUUCGAACACAUGAAUGGGCUCACACUGGGGGGAAACCUUAUGAUUGUGAGGAAUGUGGAAAAAGCUUUAUUUCCCGUUCAAGCAUUCGAAGACACAGGAUAAUGCACAGUGGAGAUGGACCCUACAAAUGUAACUUUUGUGGGAAAGCCUUGAUGUGUCUCAGUUUGUAUCUUAUCCACAAACGAACUCACACUGGAGAGAAACCAUAUGAAUGUAAACAGUGUGGUAAAGCCUUUAGUCAUUCUGGUAGCCUUCGAAUACAUGAAAGAACUCACACUGGAGAGAAGCCUUAUGAAUGCAGUGAGUGUGGGAAAGCAUUCCAUAGUUCCACAUGCCUCCAUGCACAUAAAAUAACUCACACUGGGGAGAAGCCGUAUGAAUGUAAACAGUGUGGGAAAGCCUUUGUUUCUUUCAAUUCCGUUCGAUAUCAUGAAAGAACUCACACUGGAGAGAAGCCCUAUGAAUGUAAGCAAUGUGGGAAAGCCUUCAGAUCUGCCUCGCACCUUCGAACACAUGGAAGGACUCACACUGGAGAGAAACCCUAUGAAUGUAAACAAUGUGGUAAAGCCUUUGGAUGUGCCUCGAGCGUUAAAAUCCAUGAAAGGACUCACACUGGAGAAAAACCCUGUAGCUCCAACACUUCGAAAGGCCAAGGCGAGAAGAUUGCUUAAUUCACAUAAGAUUCCUAGAAGCCACCGAAUCCAAUCAUGGUAAAAAUGUGUUUCCCUCAAAUCAUGGGAACCAUCGCAAAAUUAUUCUGAAGCUUCUGCAGUCACUGUCAUUUGACAGCAUUCAGAAAUAAAUGCCAGUAGCCCAGGAGCAAAAAUUUUUGGGAGUAGUUUAGCUGGGGCCUCACUCAGAUACCUAGGACACAGAGUUGGAAAUAACUCUUAAGAGAGACACACCUCCAGUAAGACCUUAAGACAGUUCUGUCAUAAAAAAAAUACGAGGUUUGGCCGGGUGCAGUGGCUCAUGCCUAUAAUCCCAGCACUUUGGGAGGCCGAGGCAGGCGGACCACGAGGUCAGUAGUUCGAGACCAGCCUGGUCAAUAUGGUGAAACCCCAUCUCUACUAAAAAA